CUUCAAAUAUGUUUUAACUUUUAUAAUCACUGGGAAUAUAAACAUGAAUAGCUUCCUUAACUGUGAAUCAGAACACUCAAUCAGCAAUGCUGAAUACAACCUCAGUCACUGAAUUUCUCCUUUUGGGAGUGACAGACAUUCAAGAACUGCAGCCUUUUCUCUUCGUUGUUUUCCUUACCAUCUACUUCAUCAGUGUGGCUGGGAAUGGAGCCAUUCUGAUGAUUGUCAUCUCUGAUCCUAGACUCCAUUCCCCUAUGUAUUUCUUCCUGGGAAACCUGUCCUGCCUGGACAUCUGCUACUCCAGCGUAACACUGCCAAAAAUGCUGCAGAACUUCCUCUCUGCACACAAAGCAAUUUCUUUCUUGGGAUGCAUAAGCCAACUCCAUUUCUUCCACUUCCUGGGCAGCACAGAGGCCAUGUUGUUGGCCGUGAUGGCAUUUGACCGCUUUGUGGCUAUUUGCAAGCCACUUCGCUACACUGUCAUUAUGAACCCUCAGCUCUGUACCCAGAUGGCCAUCACAAUCUGGAUGAUUGGUUUUUUCCAUGCCCUGCUGCACUCCCUAAUGACCUCUCGCUUGAACUUCUGUGGUUCUAACCGUAUCUAUCACUUCUUCUGUGAUGUGAAGCCAUUGCUAAAGCUGGCCUGUGGGAACACUGAGCUUAAUCAGUGGCUGCUCAGUACUGUCACAGGGACAAUCGCCAUGGGCCCCUUCUUUCUCACAUUACUCUCCUAUUUCUACAUUAUCACCCAUCUCUUCUUCAAGACUCAUUCUUUUAGCAUGCUCCGCAAAGCACUGUCCACUUGUGCCUCCCACUUCAUGGUAGUUAUUCUUUUGUAUGCACCUGUUCUCUUCACCUAUAUUCAUCAUGCCUCAGGGACCUCCAUGGACCAGGACCGGAUCACUGCCAUCAUGUAUACUGUGGUCACUCCAGUACUAAACCCACUGAUCUACACUUUGAGGAACAAGGAAGUGAAAGGGGCCUUUAAUAGAGCAAUGAAAAGGUGGCUUUGGCCUAAAGAAAUCUUGAAGAACUCUUCUGAAGCAUAAAUAAACAAUUAAAAAGAUGAGUUUGUAAUUACAUUGUUUCUUAAAUUAUUUAGAAAUGUACAACAGAGGGAACUGGAUAAAACAAAAAUAUAUGGAAAAAUAUGCUGUAGUUGUAUUUAACAAUGCUUUCCUGGAUUAUAUAAGGGACAUUUGAAUGAAUGGGAUACUAGCCAUGGAACUCUACUGCUGACUAUGUUUUGAAGAUAUCAGUUGAUAAAAUUGAUGUUAGGUUUUUUAUAUGUUCUUAUGAUGAAAUUGGGUAUAGAAAUAUGCCUGUUUUUCCCAUAUAUCAAAUAUAUGGAUAAUACUUGGGUCUAUUUAUCUAUCUGGUCCCUCUAGGUUAAUGCAUUAUAAUAUUAUAAAUAAAAUUAUUAUGCUUUGAUGUUUUGAGGAUUUUACUUUAGGGCCAUAGUUACUCAACUGGAAAAGAAUAUGCUAACUGACGUAUGAGUUAAGGAGAAUUUUUAAGGGGUGGGUCUUGAUUUCUUAUUCUUCAAACAAGGAGACAAGUAAUUAAAGCAAAUGACAUUGUAAUCACUAAAUAACAACAACAACAAAAACCCUGACAGUUCAUCUAAAUAGUUUUGGCACCUCUGUCUCCACAUAUCUCUUAUUAGUCAACUGUCCACACCCUCAAUGAUUACUUAAAAUAUUAAAAAUCGGAGAUAAUUUAACAAAG